GUCAGGAUGAGGAGGCGGAGGUCGGCGGUCGGGUCCGUCUCUGCCCGCGGCUGUGGCGGCGCCGGCGGAUCCAGCCUUAGCGGUUUCUCUCUGGGCGGCGGCGGCGGCGGCUCGGUUGACGCCUCCUCCGCCAGCUGAGCCCGCGGGAGCCCAGGACGCCGCUUCCCCGCCCAUCCCCGCUCCCCGAGGCCGGCCGCCUGGUCAUGGCGCAGCCGGGCCCGGCUUCCCAGCCUGACGAUUGCUUACAGAUUUCAACGUAUAAAUGAACAGUGUGACUGCAUAAAAGAAGAACAUCCCUAGGAGGUGGUAUUACACCGUUUACAACUUCUGCUCAUGUGACUCAUGAAUCUCCUCUAUUAAACACCUGUAAUCAUGGGGAAAUCCAGCUAGGCCUUGGAACCAGGCAGUUUCUCUUCAGCAACGGGUAGCAGAAUUGGAAAAAAUUAAUGCAGAAUUUUUACGUGCACAACAGCAGCUUGAACAAGAAUUUAAUCAAAAGAGAGCAAAAUUUAAGGAGUUAUAUUUGGCUAAAGAGGAGGAUCUGAAGAGGCAAAAUGCAGUAUUACAAGCUGCACAAGAUGAUUUGGGACACCUUCGAACCCAGCUGUGGGAAGCUCAAGCAGAGAUGGAGAAUAUUAAGGCGAUUGCCACAGUCUCUGAGAACACCAAGCAAGAAGCUAUAGAUGAAGUGAAAAGACAGUGGAGAGAAGAAGUUGCUUCACUUCAGGCUGUUAUGAAAGAAACAGUUCGUGACUAUGAGCACCAGUUCCACCUUAGGCUGGAGCAGGAGCGAACACAGUGGGCACAGUAUAGAGAAUCCGCAGAGAGGGAAAUAGCUGAUUUAAGAAGAAGGCUGUCUGAAGGUCAAGAGGAGGAAAAUUUAGAAAAUGAAAUGAAAAAGGCCCAAGAGGAUGCUGAGAAACUUCGGUCCGUUGUGAUGCCAAUGGAAAAGGAAAUUGCAGCUUUGAAGGAUAAACUGACAGAGGCUGAAGACAAAAUUAAAGAGCUGGAGGCCUCAAAGGUUAAAGAACUGAAUCAUUAUCUGGAAGCUGAGAAAUCUUGUAGGACUGAUCUAGAGAUGUAUGUAGCUGUUUUGAAUACUCAGAAAUCUGUUCUACAGGAAGAUGCUGAGAAACUGCGGAAAGAAUUGCAUGAAGUUUGCCAUCUCUUGGAGCAAGAGCGACAACAACACAACCAGUUAAAACAUACGUGGCAGAAGGCCAAUGACCAGUUUCUGGAAUCUCAGCGUUUACUGAUGAGAGACAUGCAGCGAAUGGAGAUUGUGCUAACUUCAGAACAGCUCCGACAAGUUGAAGAACUGAAGAAGAAAGAUCAGGAGGAUGAUGAACAACAAAGACUCAAUAAGAGAAAGGAUCACAAAAAAGCAGAUGUUGAGGAAGAAAUAAAAAUACCAGUAGUGUGUGCUUUAACUCAAGAAGAAUCUUCAGCCCAGUUAUCAAAUGAAGAGAAAACACCAUUCAAAAUAAAAAUAACUGAUAGAUCAUCCUACCCAGAGGUAACAACUAAUAUUUUGGAGCAUUUAGACAGCACCCGUGGCUCAGUUCAUUCCUUAGAUGCAGGCUUGCUGUUGCCAUCUGGAGAUCCUUUCAGUAAAUCGGACAAUGACAUGUUUAAAGAUGGACUCAGGAGAGCACAGUCUACAGACAGCUUGGGAACCUCGGGCUCAUUGCAAUCCAAAGCUUUAGGCUAUAACUACAAAGCAAAAUCUGCUGGAAACCUGGACGAGUCAGAUUUUGGACCACUGGUAGGAGCAGAUUCAGUGUCUGAGAACUUUGAUACUGCAUCCCUUGGGUCACUCCAGAUGCCAAGUGGGUUUAUGUUAACCAAAGAUCAGGAAAGAGCAAUCAAGGCGAUGACACCAGAACAAGAAGAGACAGCGUCCCUCCUCUCCAGCGUUACCCAGGGCAUGGAGAGUGCCUAUGUGUCCCCUAGUGGUUAUCGUUUAGUUAGUGAAACAGAAUGGAAUCUCUUGCAGAAAGAGGUACAUAAUGCUGGAAAUAAACUUGGUAGACGUUGUGAUAUGUGUUCCAAUUACGAAAAACAGUUACAAGGAAUUCAGAUUCAGGAGGCUGAAACGAGAGACCAGGUGAAAAAACUACAGCUGAUGCUAAGGCAAGCUAAUGACCAGUUAGAGAAGACAAUGAAAGAUAAGCAGGAGCUGGAAGACUUCAUAAAGCAAAGCAGCGAAGAUUCGAGUCACCAGAUCUCUGCACUCGUCCUAAGAGCCCAGGCCUCCGAGAUCUUACUUGAAGAGUUACAGCAGGGGCUUUCCCAGGCAAAGAGGGAUGUUCAGGAACAGAUGGCGGUGCUGAUGCAGUCACGGGAACAGGUUUCAGAAGAGCUGGUGAGGUUACAGAAAGAUAAUGACAGUCUCCAGGGAAAGCACAGCCUGCAUGUGUCAUUACAGCAAGCAGAAGACUUCAUCCUCCCAGACACUACAGAGGCACUGCGGGAGUUGGUAUUAAAAUACCGUGAGGACAUCAUUAAUGUGCGGACAGCAGCAGACCACGUAGAAGAAAAGCUGAAGGCUGAGAUACUUUUCCUAAAAGAGCAGAUCCAAGCAGAACAGUGUUUAAAAGAAAAUCUUGAAGAAACUCUGCAACUAGAAAUAGAAAACUGCAAGGAGGAAAUAGCUUCUAUUUCUAGCCUAAAAGCUGAAUUAGAAAGAAUAAAAGUGGAAAAAGGACAGUUGGAGUCCACAUUAAGAGAGAAGUCUCAACAGCUUGAGAGUCUUCAGGAAAUAAAGAUCAGUUUGGAAGAGCAGUUAAAGAAAGAGACUGCUGCUAAGGCUACCGUUGAACAACUAAUGUUUGAAGAGAAGAAUAAAGCUCAGAGAUUACAGACAGAAUUAGAUGUCAGUGAGCAAGUCCAGAGGGAUUUUGUAAAGCUUUCACAGACCCUUCAGGUGCAGUUAGAGCGGAUCCGGCAAGCUGACUCCUUGGAGAGAAUCCGGGCAAUUCUGAAUGAUACUAAACUGACAGACAUUAACCAGCUUCCUGAGACAUGACACCCUCAUGGCAGGAUUCUAGCCUGCACUUUGGGUUUUUAACUCAUCUUUAGAGCAACAGUAAUUAUUAUUUAACUCUUAACUGAAGAAAGAGAAGUCACAACAAAAGGAAGACUGGAGAAAUGCUUACUUCUAGAGGGAGAAGACUGUGCGGCACAGGAAACAGCAAACAGUGGGGUGAUCUGCAGCCCAGAGACCUUCAAAUGCGAACACUAUAAACUCCAGGCUUGAUUCCAACAGGCGUGGGAUCAGAUUUGGUGAUGGAAAAAGCGCUGUUUCCUUGCCUGCUUUCUCCAAGACAGAUUUUCGGAACACAUUUCCCUACCCUAAAGCGACAUCCCAGUAGUGUUUGGAAUUUUCUGUUCAUAGAUAUUGGAAGAGAGAAUUUGCUUUAUCUGUUGUCUAGAGCUCAUCAGUAACAGUAUUCAGUUAGCAGACAGAAGUGUAGUAUGCUGUAUGAAUAUUUUAUAUUAAAAUAUGAAGGUUUGAGAGCAGGCCAUUGGCUACUGACUGUAUUUUGUUUUCCUUUUACCAUUUUAUCUUAUCUUGCUUUGGAGGACCUUAAAUGCUACUGAAACUUACCUGAGAACCAUAGGACUGUGGCAAACAAAACCAAUUCAUGAAGUGAAUUAAUGAUGAGGAUCUGAAAACUUGGCUGGGGCUAUAUAUACUGGAAGUUGAAGGUUAAAGGAAAAGCACAAGAAACUUUGGAAGCACUUUUUCUGCAUACUUAGAUGAUCUUCAUGGGCCCACAGGGUACCAGGAUAAAGCCGAACUGGUACCAUCUACUCUUUUGAAGUGUUUUAGUCUAGUUAUUGGAUCAGUGAAAAACAUUAGUAUACGUUUUUAAAUAGGCUAAUUUUUCAACUUGGAUCAUUAGGCUUACGUACUACUUGUUUCAAAUGUGUCAAAUACAAAAAUGGUAACUAGGUUGACAGAUACUUUGUAUUUUUCUUUUGAAUUCAGACCUGGAAUGUAAGUAAGUGACAAUGCUUAUGGAAAGCCAGUUAGUUAGAAUUGGAAAUCUGUCUUGUCAUUUUACAAGCAUUAGAUUCCUUUCCUGUGUGAAGAAAGCCUCAGUGAAACAGGUCUUUGCCAUAACUUUAUGAAGUGCUACAGAAAGCACAAAGAAUUGAUUCAUGUUCAUCAAUACCUGCUGAGAGUACUGUCCCAGGAAUAUCCAGUGGAUGGAUUCAUCAUCCAGGAGGUUCAAAAGUAAGAUGGUUUUCAAAUCAUUUUUGAGACUGGUUGCAUAACAGCAGGGUACCUGAAAGAGCCUUCUGGGAGUUAGUGAACUAGGUAGAUUGUUUUGUUCACAUAACGCCACCAUCAACUUAAAGUGAAUUGUCUUUGUUAUAAAUGAGGUCACUAUGGACUUACCCUAAAGAUCUUCUGUACUUCUGUCUUCCAUAGGACAAAUGAUAAGUACUACAUACCUCAUCUCUUGGGUUAUUAUUGUAGUCUUGCAUUCAUGGUUAUGAAUUUAAAAAUAAAUACCAAUUAUGGAAAUAGUACUAAAGGCUUGCCGCACAUGAAACAUUAUUUUAAUUGGUUUAAAGUCCCUUUAUAAAGAGUGCUACAUGGUUUAGAUAAAGGAAACAUAUAACUAUUGAGUUACAGGGGAUUUUAUUAAUUAUAAAAUGCAAUCAAUUUAAAUUACGUAGGUUUAAGACUAGUCCCUUGGAUAAGCCCCAAGCGAAUUUGUCUUCAGAUUAUUAAAAUUAGUGCUGUAAAUCAGGGUGGGCAAUUCACAGCCUUUCUGAACUGACUGAACUAGAGCUUGCAGUGAAGUGUUCUGCUGAGACUGAGCACCUUACAGAUAUUUUUCUCCAGAAGAUGGUGCUGGGUAAUAAAAUCAUCACAAUUAGGGAAUGGUUAGUGGUCUCUACUGUGGCAAAUGCCAACUGUUGGAAUUCACUUUAUUGUAGAAAAACCCAAACUGAGACUCUUAAGUUUUGUUUAGCAAUGUGUUUCUGGUAUGAAACAAACUACUGUGUCACUGUCCAGGUAGGAAACAAUUCUUUCAACUGGGUUUUCAGCAUAAAUGGGAACUGAUGUAGAAGGCAGGAUUUAGCCCUUCUAGGCAAAAGAAAAGCUCAGUUGGGUUUCACGAGUGUUCCUGUGCUUAUAUUCAGUCUGUGCCUACAUGUUCUCAUGCAUGUCUAACCUGAUUUACCUCUUACCUGUAACCUACCUUAUCAUGUGGCUUUUAAUUGACAGUCACUCAGCCAUUUCUAAGCAGAUAUAGUAGUACCUUUCAGAACUCACAUUGGCAAGUGUAAAAAGAUGACUUAAGGUGAAGUGAGGACAAAAUCACAUUCUGCAUACUAACCUAUUUUUUUCUCCCUUUAAGGUGCUAAACUUGCACCUCAUGUCCACUCAGUAACAAGUAUUGGGACGUAGAGCACAGCCUCACUCAGCUCUGAAAGGUAAUACAGCUUGUGAGGAAGUGAGCCAGCAGUGGCCUUUGCAAUUGUGGAUCUUGAGCUCUGCUCUCAGCAGAUUUCAGGUGUAACCAUUUGUUAACUGUACUGAAGGUGUGUCCUCAAGAAGAAAGUGUUCAAAUUAAAAAAGCUGCUGCCAAGUACACUGUGUGGUCUUCUCCUUUGAAUCCUAGGGUUCUAUCCCUCUUCAGAGUCAUGUUUCUGGUGCUGCUACUUUAAAACACAGCUCACAAGAAUAACUAACUUGCUCAAAUAUGGAGAAAACUCAAUAGGGUUCAGGGAGGUUCUGGCAGUGUGCAGUGUGAAAUAAUCCUGAGUCCUUGCUGAACACAACUGUAGGCUUGAGUUAUAAAGCACAUUCCAAAUUUUAAAUAAAAGCAUUUACUCAAUUAUUAUAAAACAACAUAUUUAAAAAGAUGAACCACACCAAAGGUCAUCAAAACACCUUUUUAUAAAUUAGAUAAUUCUACCUGUUUUACAAUAUGGGUUUAAGCCUUCAAUGGUGUUCAGUUCAGGUGUGAGUCAGCUCCUGGUGGUGUCAGAAGUUUACAUGAUUGCGGAUAUCAUUGAUUUGCUUCACCAUUUCCCUUAUAUGUUCACCCCUGUAAAAUUGUAAAGUCACUCACUUUUGGAAUUAUAAUAAACCAUUUAUAUGGAUUCUUAAGAAUUUAAA